GGGUUGUUUUUGCUUUUUGGCUGUUAUAAAUAAUGCUGCUAUGGACACUUGUGUACAACACAAGCUUUUGUGUAAACAUAUUUUUUUCAGUUUUCUUGGGUCUAUCCCUAGGAGUGGAAUUGCUGAAUCAUGUAACAGUUCUAUGUUUAACUUUUUGAGGAACCACCAAACUUUUUCAUCAUAGCUAUACCAUUUUAUUAUAUUCCCGUUAGCAAUGUAUGAAUGUUCCAAUUUCACCACAUCUUUUCAAUACUUGUUAUUGCCUUUUUUUAAAAAAAAAGUUAUUAUUAUGUCUAUCCUUGUGGAUAUGAAAUAGUAUUUUGUUGUGAUUUUGAUUUGCAUUUCACUAAAUGACUUAUGAUGUUGAGUAUCUUUUCAUGUAAUUAUUGGCCAAUUAUAUCUCUGAACCUGAAGAAAUAUCUAUUCAAAUCCUUUGCCAAUUUAAAAAUUAGAGUAUUUGUCUUUUUAUUGUUGAGCUGAAAGAGUCCUUUCUAUUCUCUCAUCAGAUAUAUGAUUAGCAAAUUUUUUUUUCCAUUCUGUAGAUUGUUUUUCCACUUUCUUAAGGCUGUUCUUUGAAACAGUGUUUUUAAUUUUGAUGAUGUCUAGUUUAUUUUAUCAUCUGUGGAUUGUGCUUUUGGUGUCAUAUCUAAAAAACAUUGCCUAGUCCAAAGUCAUGAAGACUUACACUCCUAUAUUUUUUUCUAAGAGUUUUAUAAUCUUAGCUCUUACUUUUAUGUCUCUGAUCCAUUUUGACUUAAUUUUUGUAUGUGGUAUGAGGUAGGGGUCCAACUUUAUUAUUUUUCAUGUGGCUAUUCAGUUAUCCUGGCCCCAUUUAUUGAAAAGACCAUUUUUUCCCAUCGAAUUAUUUGGUCACUUUUAUCAAAUGUCAAUUUACCAGAAAUAUAAAGGUUUAUUUCUAGAUUCUCAGUUCUACUCCAUUAAUCUAUAUCUGUCCUUAUGCCAAUACCACCCUUUCUUAAUUAGUAUGACUUUGUGGUAAGUUUUGAAAUUAGGAAAUGUGAUUCCAAUUUUGUUCUUCUCUUUGAAGAUUGUUUUGGCCAUUCUGAGUCCUUUGCAUUUAAUGAAUCUUAGGGUAAUUUUGUUAAUUUAUACAAAAUAGAUAGCUGGGAUUUUGAUAGGAAUUGCAUCAAAUCUGUAGCUUUGUAGAUUAUUUACACCCUUUUUUUUUUUUUUUUUCGGACAGGGUCUCAAUUGCUUGAGCUGGAGUGCAGUGGUGUAAUCAUGGCUUACUACAGCCUUGACCUCCUGGGCUCAGGUGAUCCUCUUUCCUCAGCCUCCUAAGUGGCUGGAGCUACAGGCAUGCUCCACUUUUUCUAUUUUUUUUGUAGAGACAGGGUUUCACCAUGUUGCCCAGGCUAGUCUUGAACUCCUGAGCUCAAGCUGUUCACCUGCCUUGGUCUCCCAAAGUGCUAGGAUUAGAGAUGUGAGCCACUGCGCCUGGCCCUAUUGACAUCUUAAUAAGUCUUCCAAUUCAUGAUCAUGGGAUAUCUUUCCAUUUAUUUAGACCUCCUUUAACUUCUUUCAGUGAUGUUUUGUAGCAUCUGUAUAUUGAACCUCAUUUUACCAUGCAUUAAUUACAGGGUAAAGUAGCUAAUGAGAAGAAAUGAGUUUAACUUUCCUUAAAAUAUCUGACCUGAUCUCAUUAAGUUGAGUUGUAUACUGAUAUUCAACUAUUUUUGAUAUAUAAAAUCAGCAAUUUCAUGUUUCAGUUUAACACUUUUAUUGCUUGACCAUAUGCUAAUGAGAUUAAUACAUCAAUUAAGCUAAGCUGCUAUUACAAAGAGGCAUACAGAUAUGGAGGCUUAGAUAGGAUAGAAGCAUAUUCUCUUUCAAAAACUAGCUAAAUAGCCCAGGCUAGCAGGGCAACUGUGCCCCAUGAGAUCGUUUAGGAACCUAGGUUCUUUUAGAUUCCCUCAGUGCAUUGACCUUGACCGAAUGGUUAAAUUGGGUGACUGUUAUGUGUGUAUUACAAUUUUCAUAAAAGAGGAAGGAGAACUUACUCAUGGCAAGCGCAGUUUAUCUUUAAUUUGGAAACUAUCCAGAAGUUGUACACAUCUCUGCACACCCAAUUGCCUGCACUUGGUUAUGUGGGCACACCUGGCUCCAAGGGAGGCAGAAAAAUGUACGUUCUAGCUGGACAACUGUGUGCCCCACUAUGGAAGACAGGAAGGGUGGAUUUGAGGGGACAAGCAGCCACUUGUCACACUCAACUCUCUCUUGCCUUUUUUAAUGGAAAACCAUGAUUUCUCAGUAACAUGAUUGUUUUCUACCUCCAGUAUUCCCACUAGGUUUCUUCUCCCAGCCUAACCCUGAAAUUGCUCAGGUUUUACUGUCACACACUCCAGAGGUUUCUGCUGGUGACGAUUUGGACAGAGUUGUGUCAUGUAUCCAAGUACCUUCGUACCUUCCCAGUGGGAAGGGAAAGCACAAAUGCCGCAUGUAGAGUCUUCUCAGGAUGACAGAAAUUGUAGACAGGGAAAGACAAGGCCAUUGCAGAGCUUUUUUCUCCACCGAAAGAACAAGGGCAGGACCUUUCAACUUUUACCCUAAGUAUCCUUGUUGUAAGACUAACCUCUAGGUCUUGCCCUAUAACCAUGAUCCUAAAAGCAGGCUUGAAGGAAGAGCCUCUGGUGAGAGGCAUCUGAUGAAAUUAUUCUACUCUCUAGAGGAAAUCACUUGGAGGUAAACCUCAAAUCAGAAGCACUUUGGAUGAUGUGUCUUGGAUAUUGUCACAUGGUCUGCCAGCAGGUCUCUAGUUGCUCUAGUCUAGACUUGUUCCCAGGACUUAAGCCUCCUGACCCAGUUUGGUUGAUGAUUGUGGUUUGAAAACAUAAUUCACCCUGCUCCCUUUCAGCUGUCUUAGCUUCUAUGCUGCAGGAUUUCCUUCAAAGCACAAUUUAUAACCCAUUAAAUGGGCCUUUCAUUCCUUCUUCCUCAGGCUUACCCAUCUAAGUAGCUCCAAAUGGUCUCUCACCUUUAGCAGAGGAAAAUGUGUGCCCACUGCUGUACAUACAGCAAUGCUUGUACACUGGUAACAGUUGUUACCACCUACAAAUGCUUAAGGGCUAGGGUCUGUGGUAAAUGUUAUACAUCUUCUAUAGUCUUCACAAGAAUUCCCCAAAGUAGGGAUCAUCAUUUCCAUUUUACAGAUGAGGUAACUGGGCUCAGACAAUUGAAGUCACAUGCCUAAGUUCACCCAGGUGGCAGACAUAAAGCUAUGAUUAGAACUAGAUAUGUGUGUAGUGACAAUCUGUGCUUGUAGUUAUGCCACCAUCUGUAUGGUCCUGUUCCUGCACUUAAGGCAGCCUCUUCUGAAUGAUCAGCCCACCGUGCGUGCCUAGGGCCCAGCAGGGUGUCUCAGGGAGGGCCAGGGCAUGCCUAGGAACUUGGUACAAAGCUGUUUCCCAAACUGACUUGUAACUCACUGACUCAUUCAAGAAGUGUCUGUGGAAUGCUUGCCCUAUGCCAGGUACUGGCUGAGUCUGAGUGCCCCACACCUCAACCCUCCUGGAACUCAUCCAGAGCUGGGGGCCUCUGCGCCUCUGCUAUUCCAGGUGCCCAGGGCCAUCUGGUUUGUCUUCCUGCUCUUUGAGUGUGCUUCUAAAGUUCUCCUGCAAAUGUUGUGAUGGAGGGUGAGAUGAUAAAGGGCUGGAUCCUCAAUUGUGUAAGUUUCCCAGUCUGCUUGGAUUGGGGACUGCCUCAAGAAGGCUAUUGCUGAAAUUGUUCCCUUUCUUUGCGCUGUGUGGGUAGAGCAGUGGUUACUGUCAGAGGGCAUCGUCCCACAAGGCCUUCUUGCCUGUUGGUUGUGGGAUGAGGUGGAGGCAUUGUCUUAAUCAUUUUAAGUUUAAAAAAUUACAAUAGUGGCUGGGCACGGUGGCUUACACCUGUAAUCUCAGCACUUUGGGAGGCUGAGGCGGGCAGAUCACAAGGUCAGGAGAUCGAGACCAUCCUGGCUAACAUGGUGAAACCCCAUCUCUACUAAAAAUACAAAAAAUUAGCCGGGCAUGGUGCUGGGUGCCUGUAGUCCCAGCUACUCCUGAGGCUGAGGCGGGAGAAUGGUGUGAACCCGGGAGGUGGAGCUUGCAGUGAGCUGAGAUCGCACCACUGCACUCCAGCCUGGGCGACAGAGCAAGACUCUGUCUCAAAAUUACAAUAGCAAAACGUUUUCUGUAGAAAAAAUUUGAAAAUAUGGGUAAACAAGAAAGAAAAGAUAGGGAAAGAAAAUCACCCUGAACCCACUUAUAGAGAUAAUGCGUAUUGAUAUUUGGGUGUGUUUACUCCUAUUCAUGUGCUCAUCUGCCUAUCCCUAGUGGGAUCUUUCUGUUUUAAAAGUUGCUUUUUGAAUGUAAUAUAGCAUGAACACAUAACCACAUUAAUAAAUAUGUUGUUAUGUCAAUAAGUUUAUCAAUGUAUAUAUUACAUAUAUGUUAAUAAAUACAUCAUCAUUUUGAAUGAGGGUUCAGUUAAUAAGAAGAAGAAUUAUAUGCUACUUUCAAUUUACAAAGUGCUUUCACAUAUAUUAGUUCAAUUAUCUUUGUCAAAGAUUAUUAAACAGUCAGUGUGGUUCCUGGAAUGUGGAAUCAUAGAUAAUUACCAAGUGCAAGACAUUCCCCAGCCCACCUCAUUCAAGGGAGACUGGUCACCUCCUUUCAGAGCAUGGACCCUGACCUGACAGUCUAGAGAUGGUGCAGGUUACUACAAAAUAGAGCUCUGGCCCAGCACAGGCAUGGAGUUGCUGUGCCUUUUGUCAAGAAAGGUAGCUGUCCACUUUUCCUCACUUUGAAAAAAAAAUCAAACACCCCUCCUCCACCUCUGAUCCUAGGAAAUGGUUGAAGGGAUUACCAAGCCUCGGGAGGUGGUUAAUUAUUAACUCAAGAGUAAAUUUUGUGAGGGUUGGGUUAGGCAGUGAGGACUUUUAGGAAAUUACUGGCAGCACUGUGGGAGCUGGUGGGUCUGUGUUGCGGGGAGGUACUCAGAGGCAGUGACUUAGCUGAACGAGUUCUUCCAGGCUGCUUGCAAAUGGUCAUCAAAGGACUUGUUGACCUUUUAACCUUGGGAGGGCAACUAAGUUGACUAAACCUGAGGUAAAUCACAUCAACUUCUACUGCCCGCCUUUCCCUGAGCUCAGAUCCACGUAAACUUGUAUUUCUCUUGAAUUUCUCCAGUCUUUUUUCCCACCAACAGAAUACCAAGUCUUCAUUUAUAUCACCCACCUUCCAUUGUAAACAUAAAGCGGGAUGUUGGCAGAGGAAAACUAGUUUAGUCAGCCCCAGAAAGACUUCUUCUCUGAAUGCCAGUGUCCCUCAGCAAAGCUCUCACCAACACUGUAGCUCUACAUAAGCCUCCUCAGACACAAUCUCAUUUCAGGCCCUUUUGGAGAAACCACAGGUCUACUAGCCAUAGAUGGUAAUUUCUGGAUGAGGGUUAGUUGUUGGUGUUAGUGAUUCCUUGUAACUCUUCUGUAAGGUCGGUAUUGCUGUCUUUGCUGUAGGGAUGAGGAAACUGAGGUUUGGAGAGGUGAACUUGCUUCCUAAAGGCACAUAGCUGUUAAGUGAUAAAACAGGCAUUUGACCCAAGUCUGUCUAAAUCUUUCUCUGGUAGCAUUCUGCCUACUUGGGCAGUAGUUCUCACAUUCCUUUUAGCUGUAGAACCCCUGAAGUGGGAUAGAAUGCAGACAAACAAAGAAACAAGCCAGGUAAGAGCAGAGCUGCCCUGACUGGAGCUAAUGGGGCCAGUCCCAGUCCCAUAACCCCCCACCCCUGCCUCACCCCCGACAUGCUUCCAGGCGGUCUGAGACACCUUCACAGGACACUGAGAGCUUAGUGUGAAAACUGUCACAGAAGGGAUGCAGGGACACAAACAGAACAUAUUUGGAUCUUUGAAACACUCUAUGAUCUUUCCAGCUAUGGGGUGCUACUUUGGGAGUUGCUGACUGGUGAGGUGCCCUUUCGAGGCAUUGAUGGCUUAGCAGUCGCUUAUGGAGUGGCCAUGAACAAACUCGCCCUUCCUAUUCCUUCUACGUGCCCAGAACCUUUUGCCAAACUCAUGGAAGACUGCUGGAAUCCUGAUCCCCACUCACGACCAUCUUUCACGAAUAUCCUGGACCAGCUAACCACCAUAGAGGAGUCUGGUUUCUUUGAAAUGCCCAAGGACUCCUUCCACUGCCUGCAGGACAACUGGAAACACGAGAUUCAGGAGAUGUUUGACCAACUCAGGGCCAAAGAAAAGGAACUUCGCACCUGGGAGGAGGAGCUGACGCGGGCUGCACUGCAGCAGAAGAACCAGGAGGAACUGCUGCGGCGUCGGGAGCAGGAGCUGGCCGAGCGGGAGAUUGACAUCCUGGAACGGGAGCUCAACAUCAUCAUCCACCAGCUGUGCCAGGAGAAGCCCCGGGUGAAGAAACGCAAGGGCAAGUUCAGGAAGAGCCGGCUGAAGCUCAAGGAUGGCAACCGCAUCAGCCUCCCUUCUGAUUUCCAGCACAAGUUCACGGUGCAGGCCUCCCCUACCAUGGAUAAAAGGAAGAGUCUUAUCAACAGCCGCUCCAGUCCUCCUGCAAGCCCCACCAUCAUUCCUCGCCUUCGAGCCAUCCAGUGUGAGACUGUUUCCCAAAUUAGCUGGGGCCAGAACACACAGGGGCACCUGUCCCCUGCUCUGUCCAGCCACCGACUGGUCCAGGCUUGCUCCAUCCAUAACUUCUGCCACCUCUCCUCGACAAUGUGUAUAUACAUGCACAUAUUGACACCAGGUGAAAGCAGCAAAACCUGGGGCAGGAGCUCAGUCGUCCCAAAGGAGGAAGGGGAGGAGGAGGAGAAGAGGGCCCCAAAGAAGAAGGGACGGACGUGGGGGCCAGGGACGCUUGGUCAGAAGGAGCUUGCCUCGGGAGAUGAAGGAUCCCCUCAGAGACGUGAGAAAGCUAAUGGUUUAAGUACCCCAUCAGAAUCUCCACAUUUCCACUUGGGCCUCAAGUCCCUGGUAGAUGGAUAUAAGCAGUGGUCGUCCAGUGCCCCCAACCUGGUGAAGGGCCCAAGGAGUAGCCCGGCCCUGCCAGGGUUCACCAGCCUUAUGGAGAUGGCCUUGCUGGCAGCCAGUUGGGUGGUGCCCAUCGACAUUGAAGAGGAUGAGGACAGUGAAGGCCCAGGGAGUGGAGAGAGUCGCCUACAGCAUUCACCCAGCCAGUCCUACCUCUGUAUCCCAUUCCCUCGUGGAGAGGAUGGCGAUGGCCCCUCCAGUGAUGGAAUCCAUGAGGAGCCCACCCCAGUCAACUCGGCCACGAGUACCCCUCAGCUGACGCCAACCAACAGCCUCAAGCGGGGCGGUGCCCACCACCGCCGCUGCGAGGUGGCUCUGCUCGGCUGUGGGGCUGUUCUGGCAGCCACAGGCCUAGGGUUUGACUUGCUGGAAGCUGGCAAGUGCCAGCUGCUUCCCCUGGAGGAGCCUGAGCCACCAGCCCGGGAGGAGAAGAAAAGACGGGAGGGUCUUUUUCAGAGGUCCAGCCGUCCUCGUCGGAGCACCAGCCCCCCAUCCCGAAAGCUUUUCAAGAAGGAGGAGCCCAUGCUGUUGCUAGGAGACCCCUCUGCCUCCCUGACGCUGCUCUCCCUCUCCUCCAUCUCCGAGUGCAACUCCACACGCUCCCUGCUGCGCUCCGACAGCGAUGAAAUUGUCGUGUAUGAGAUGCCAGUCAGCCCAGUCGAGGCCCCUCCCCUGAGUCCAUGUACCCACAACCCCCUGGUCAAUGUCCGAGUAGAGCGCUUCAAACGAGAUCCUAACCAAUCUCUGACUCCCACCCAUGUCACCCUCACCACCCCCUCGCAGCCCAGCAGUCACCGGCGGACUCCUUCUGAUGGGGCCCUUAAGCCAGAGACUCUCCUAGCCAGCAGGAGCCCCUCCAGCAAUGGGUUGAGCCCCAGUCCUGGAGCAGGAAUGUUGAAAACCCCCAGUCCCAGCCGAGACCCAGGUGAAUUCCCCCGUCUCCCUGACCCCAAUGUGGUCUUCCCCCCAACCCCAAGGCGCUGGAACACUCAGCAGGACUCUACCUUGGAGAGACCCAAGACUCUGGAGUUUCUGCCUCGGCCGCGUCCUUCUGCCAACCGGCAACGGCUGGACCCUUGGUGGUUUGUGUCCCCCAGCCAUGCCCGCAGCACCUCCCCAGCCAACAGCUCCAGCACAGAGACGCCCAGCAACCUGGACUCCUGCUUUGCUAGCAGUAGCAGCACUGUAGAGGAGCGGCCUGGACUUCCAGCCCUGCUCCCGUUCCAGGCAGGGCCGCUGCCCCCGACUGAGCGGACGCUCCUGGACCUGGAUGCAGAGGGGCAGAGUCAGGACAGCACCGUGCCGCUGUGCAGAGCGGAACUGAACACACACAGGCCUGCCCCUUAUGAGAUCCAGCAGGAGUUCUGGUCUUAGCACGAAAAGGAUUGGGGCGGGCAAGGGGGACAGCCAGCGGAGAUGAGGGGAGCUGGCGGGCACAGCCCUUUCUCAGGGUUGGACCCCCUGAGAUCCAGCCCUACUUCUUGCACUGAUAAUGCACUUUGAAGAUGGAAGGGAUGGAAACAGGGCCACUUCAGAGGGUCUCCUGCCCUGCAGGGCCUUUCUACCCGUGUCCACUGGAGGGGCUGUGGCCAUCAGCUCUGGCUGUGUAGGGGAGGAAGGGGUGCAUGCAUGUCCCCCACCCUCCACAGUCUUCCUUGCCUUUAGAGUGACCCUGCAGAGUCACUCAGCCAAAUCUGUCUGCUGCUCCCUCUCCUCAGCCAGUUGGGUGUGCGCAGAGCUGUCAUAGGGUCCCUUUGUCAGCCCCGAGUUCAGCUUCCCAAACACCAGUGUUGGAUAUUCUGUGAUUGAUUUUGGUCCUCCUCCGCUGUCCCCCAACACCCAGGAAUGGGAAUCUGGCUUGGUUCGAGAUAGGAGCUUUUCUGUGUCCUAAGCCCUUUCAUGCUAGCAGGAAGACUGAAAGCAAGGUGGCCCAGUGUGGGGUCAUAGGGCUUGAUAGACCUGGCACUGCCUAUCUGCACUUCCAGGUGCCCCACCUAUUUAUCUGAGCCCACAGGUGGAAAGGGGAACUGCCUCAGUGAGAACGGGGGGACGGGGAUGUUAGGAAAAAUACAGUAAAGUUGCAAUGAAGAGGUUCAUGAAGUAUGUCCUUGUUCUUUUUGGAAACUCUCGGCAAAGGGCAAACCAGCAAGUAUUGAGGGUACCCAUCUAGCUACUUGGGGUCAGGACCUCGUCAGACCAGGUUCGGAUACAAUCAUCUGCUCAUCCCAGGAAUAGUUUCUUGGGGGACUCACUCACUGGUGCCAGUUCUAAGUCAGAGACAAAAUUCCACUGUCUGUUCCUUUUGCUGUCUGAACUUUAUGUGUUACUCCCUUCCUUUGGUCUUCACUCUAAUCCCUGGAGUUUGUGGGCUUUUGGUUAUGUUUGGUUAGUAGAUAUCACCGCAAUGCCCUAGAACAGCUAUGAAGCAGAAUACCAUAUGGCCACCUGGACAUUGGGACUUGGGAAUUCACUCUCAACUGGGCCAUCCAUGUUGUGAUGCCCUUGAAGUAAAAUGGAGCCAGCAGGAGUACCUUCUGUAAAUGCAUGUGGCAAAGUGCUAUUUAUAGGGUGCCCAGGGAGCCGCUGAUGUACAAUAACCUUGAGGUCCCCCAUACUGAAAACUGACCAAGGCCUGUGCACAGGUAGCCCCUCAUGCUGGGCUCUGGACCAUGAGCUGAGUAGGAAGGAUAGCAGAGGCCAACCCUGACCUUCCUGGAAGUUGUUUCCUUAACUUGAAUGUUGAGCUUCCUCUAAAGCUUUCUCGUGUAUGUCUUCUCCAUGCCACUACUCUGAGGCCUCCUGUGUUAUGUGUGAACAGUUGUCUUUAUGUGGGAAUGACGACUUGAUUGGGAGUAGAGUCUCAAGGUCAUUCCCCUCUUCCCUCAAGACUCUCUGAAUGCUGCUCCACUGUCUUUUGUCUUGGAGGUCACUCAGCAGGUUCCUUGCAUUUGCUGCCUGGAUGUGCAGCUGGCAACAGUGAUGAAUUGGUCACUGCUCUUUCUCUAUAACUGGGAUAGAUGUCCUGCCUUGGGGUCACUAAAGGGGUGACCUUGUUCCUUGCUUUAUGAGCCCAUUAGCACUUUGGUUCAAGGGGCCCACCAAGUCUUGGACGGGAAGGCGCUACUGGUUUUAUUGCCCAAGGUUUUGUUAUUGCUUCUCUUCUGUGUCCUUCUCUUUGUUCAGUGAAGCCAAUAUGUAAGAUACUGUUUUUGUCCCCAUUCCCCUACUCCUGAGCUAGGAGGAAAAAAUGUGAAUCUUACCAGCAGUUCCAGCCAACCAAGUGAUUCUUCUUCAUUCUUGAUGGGGAGAAGUACAUACAAAGUUUGUUCUGACAGGGCGCGGUGGCUCACGCCUGUAAUCCCAGCGCUUUGGGAGGCAGAGGCAGGUGGAUCACCUGAGGUCGGGAGUUCGAGACCAGCCUGACCAACAUGGAGAUAUCCUGUCUCUACUAAAAAUACAAAAAAAUUAGCCAGGCAUGGUGGCACGUGCCUGUAAUCCCAGCUACUCGCAAGGCUGAGGCAGGAGAAUCGCUUGAACCUGGGAGGCGGAGGUUGCAGUGAGCCAAGAUUGCGCCAUUGCACUCCAGCCUGGGCAACAAGAGAGAAACUCUGUCUCAAAAAAAAAAAAAAAAAAAAAAAAAGUCUGUUCUGUGGCCUCCUUCCCCCGGGCCCUCCAUAACCUCAGGCUAAACCAUGAGCACAUCUGUAUAUCCUUGGCUCCACUAAAUGGCCCUCUUGUGGCCCUCCAAACCAUGCUGCCUAUACACAGUGCUCUGUGGUAUGAAGCAGAGAUUUUUCCUUUGCUCAUUUUUAACUUUUGCCAUUGUGGUAGGUUGCAGCCAUCUUUCUAGAUGUAGUGUAACUGAUGUAGUGUAACUGAAUGAUGGUCACCUGCCAUUGAGUGAGAGGUUGAGUGCCAUCCUUACUUGUCCACUGUGGGGAAAGAUAAAGCAAGCCUGGGUCUUUGCUAAGGAAAUAAUUGUACCUGAAAGAAGCAAAAGCAGGGCUAUCCAAAGGUGCUACUGUGAGCAUCCAUGAAGAAGGAACAGUUACCAUCUCUCAGCUCCUACACACCUGGUCUCUGAUGGGCCCCUGACUGCUGCACUCUCUCAGUGGGGCAAGGUUGGAGAUGGGCUAAGGAUCUGUAUAGUAGUAGCAGGUCUCAGUGGCUUUCUAUUCGCUCAGGUUCCCUUGUUCUGUGGUCCUGGUCGGGAGCAGGCCCUGGAGCUGUGGAUGAAGCCACUUGAGUGGCAGUAGCCGGCCCCCCUUUCCUCUGCCUUCCCUUUGCACAAAGACACGUUCCUUCUGCUCUUGGCAGGUGCUAACUUCAUGGAAGAUGGUAAUAGGAACAGAUACUGCUCUCUGCCCCUGCUUCUUGGAUUCUUCAGCUCCUACCGCUGAUUCGGAUUAUCCCCUUUUGACCCUCUUGGGGAUCCAGACUGCUGCCAGGAGGCUGAGUAGAUACCUCAGUUAUCUGUAUGUUAUUUCUGAGAGGCUUUGGCGGAUCCUCUUCACUUGGCAUCCUGUGGCAUCCCUAGGGUCUGGUGGUAGCAGUAAUAGCAACAAUGAUAUCUUACAUCUGGACAACUCAGAAUAGUGCUAACUUUUCCUCCUGACCUUUGCAAAAUGACAUCAUUUUCCUUGUACAUUUGAUACCCUUGCUAGUAGAGAAGGGGAAAUGCUUAAAGAUGAAAAUUCAAGUGAAGAGAAAUGAAAAAGUGGCUUGGACUAAUUGCUGAGUGAGGCCACUGGGCUCAGAACUGAACAGGUUGGCUGCAUUCCCCAUUCUGCUUUUGCUGUGUGGCCAUAGGCUUGUCUCUUUAGCCCCUCUCAGAUUUCCUUCCUUUAAAAGCAAUCAUCACAUGCUUUCCUCUCAAGGGAGUUGGGUGUAUGUAUCAGAGAAGGUCAGUGAAACACCAUAGCUCCUUGCCAGCUCCUAGAGGAAGCUUCUUUCAUCUAUACAGGAUGAAUCGCUGAAGUUGAGAGUGUGGCUCUCAUCACCUUUGCCUUGAGGGAACUUGCCUUUUCUUUCGUCCUUUGGCUUCUGGAAGAGGAGUGAUUUGGAGGUGGUUGAGCAUGACUAAUGGGGGCCCUGGUCGGGCCCAUGCCCUUCUGCCGCAUUUAUAUAGCAUCUGGUGUUGACAAGCAUUCUUUCCUAAUUCCCCCACUUAACUUGUCUGAUGCUGUCUGCCAAUGUCAUCCUCACCACUUGUGUCUUACAGAGAAGGAAAUGGGAGAGGGAGGUUGUGUCUUACAGAGAAGGAAAUGAGAGAGGGAGGUUGGUAGCAACAUCAGAGUGACAGUUGGCUGUCUCUCAUUUCUUGGGGUCAUCAGUCUGAUUUGUUUAGAGCCUGGGAUCAUCCCAGUUCCUGGAAGAAUCUUUGGAAAAGGGUCCCCUUGUUCUUGGGACAUGUGUCAUGGUCACUAAGCCCCCUUUCCCUCAGGCUACUGUUGCUCAGGGACACAAUGAGAUACCCCAAGGACAUCUAGACCUGACUUUUCAUGAACUCUCUUGCCUCUGUGGUCCCCACAUUGGAGACCUCCCUCCCUCCUCCUUCCCUUGUGUGAAGGAGACACCUCCCGAGCAAUCCUAACUCAUCCAGCUCACUUUUAACAAAGCAAAGAGCAGAGGGCACUGAAGACUGGAUGGCUGUGAAUGGUACACCUUGGGGUUGAAACCGUGUUGGCAGGAACCUGGUGAUAAAAGCUGCCUACUUCCUGGGUGUGUGAAUUUGCACAUAUCUUUUCCCCUCACUGGACUUCAGAAGCCUACUGUGAACUGGGGACGAUGCUAUCUACUUUCCCUCCUGAAGCCCUUCUAACUUUCAAAUGUAUGGUCCUGGGGCCAUGAGUCCUGCACAGAAACUGCAGCCUUGCCAGAUUGCUUCCCUUGGUGCAGAAAAGUGUGUGUGUGUGUGUGUGUGAAAUAUACGUACGGUUUUACGUCAAAAACAGUCGAAUAUCAGCUAUUUCAUAUGGUUCACCCUAAUGUACCUGCCUCUCUCUUUGGCUUUAGGUCUGAGAAUGACUUGUCUUUGUCAAGGUAUACUAUUGUUAGAAACGCAUUACCAAAUGCAUCUCUUCUGUCGGAUCAGCGUAUUCCUAGAUUAGGAAUUCAAAUUAAUGAAAAUUCACAUAUGAAAGGAAAAUCCAUUGCUAUUUCUGGAGAGGACCUCAGUCCUGGGCUUUUCCCUGGCAUUGCUACCUGGGUGGGUGCUCACCACUCAGGUGCUGGUGUUGGAAGGCAGGAGGAGGAAGCUGAAAUCCUGCCGAUUAAGGCUAAUUAACAGGGUUUAGGUGCCUAAUUAUCAUGACUCAGCCCGGGACUUAUGGUUAGCCGUGCAGGCCAGGUGAGUCUCUUAUGGACUUCCUCUCAGACUGCUCUUUCUCAUUUUGUCCUGAUGAGAUAUUGACAGUCAUGUCCACCCGCUUCCUCAUCCAUUUCCCGUCUUGGGCCCUGGAAGUACGGGGGCCUCUGUAGGCUGCCUAGGGAGCCCUGGCUUUGCUCUUCGUGUUGGGCUCACUCCAUGAUCAGGAGCCGGUGGGACUGGUCCUUCCUGAUUCUUACUGUCUGUGGUUCCCCAUCCCCUACGGGGAGCCUGCUUUGGGCCUUGAGCUGGAUAGAGAGAAGAGCUUUGGGGCCCAGCUGGUUAUAGGAGCUGAGCUUUUCCACACCUCUCUUUGUUAACCCUUGGAAACAGACCUGCCUUUCACCUGACCCAUCUUCCUACCUGUCUGGUCUGACCUGCCCUCUUUGAAAGCACUCAUCACCUAGUUUUACUAGGCUGAUUGGCAGAUGUGGACAUGACAGGUGUCUAUCGAGAUAGGUGUCUAACUAGUUAGGUGUCUCAGGAUUGGACAGCAGAAUACCAUUCCAGGGGUGCACAGACAGGCCUCUCCUACCGGAACAUGAGGGAUAGACGUCUGGGCAUUCUGAACCCAGAGGUCAGAGUAGUCACAAGCGGAGCCCUGGGGAGCGAGGGCCCCAGGGCCGUGGUGUUCCUUGCCCUGCGCUCACUGAAGUCCAAGGCCAGGUUUCAGAAAUAGUGUGCUGCCUGUUCCUGAGAUCCUUCACACCUGGACACCAACCCAGACAAAGCCUGACUUAAAAUUUUGAUACUGUAUUCAUCGUGGAAUUUUUCAAUAACUCUGAUUUUUAAAAAAUACUGCAUUGCAAUAUGAUUUACCUUGAUUACUGAGGCUCUUUUUUUUUUGGCACCCCUUUAAAUUUUAACCCAAGGUGAGGGCCUCACUCCACUCUAUACCCAGCCCUGCCUGCCCCUCACCUGGACCUGUGAGAGGGGCUUAGGUACCACUGUGAAAUACGUUUUAAAUUUUUACUUGCCCUUCCCCUCAGGUCCUGAGUGAGGCAGUGGCUCUCUGGCGGUGCUCGCAUUUAAAUAGGAGUGUGUAGGCUUACAGCAAUGAAACAUCUAGGAGCUUUUAACUUUGGAUCUAUACCUGGGUGUGACAUUUCCUUGGUGUUCUCUGGCUGCCUUUCUGGCUCUGCAGCCCUGAGGGCACUUGUGUGUGUGUGUGUUCUCUGGAGAAGGGAAGUGAUUAUGGCAGAGAGGCUCCUUUAGAUUCUCCUCUUAAACCUCUUUGGAACAUGUUUGAAUUCCAGAAGUGAAUGAACUUCAUUCAUUCUCUCGUCCAGAUUUCAGAAGGGACUAAAGUGAACGGAGGCUUUUUCACUCCCUGGCAUGCUAAGAGCCACAUUCCCUAGCUCUGUGCCUGCACAGUGAGUCUUCAGAAUUUGGCCCAUCACACCCUCUGCUAGUAUCGUUUCCACCACCCUCCUCAUCCUCUGUCAUCUUUAUUUCAUUCUCAUCGUUUAUCUCUACCUCCAGUUCAGAUGCCAUGCUGGCUGUGGCUCUUUUCUUCAUCACCAUCAGAGUGAGGCAAAGAUGUAUCCUGGCCUAGUUAUAAAGACGAAUAAUACAUGAUAAGAAAUCAUUAAUUUUUUUCCACGUGGGGGGCGGUGCUGUCCUAGUGAUUCAUAUAUAUAUAAUUUUUGACUCCUUACAAUAAUUCUGGGAUGUGGGUAUUACCCCCAUUUAAGAAUGUGGAAACCAAGGCUCUGAUGGCUCUGUAAUUUGCCCAGGGUCACACAGCUAGGAAGCAAGUUGCUGAUCUGCUUGGUUCCAAAGUCACCUCUCUUUUUCCUCUGAGCACAUUUCUAAGCCACUACUUAGAAGCUCUUGAGAUAAAGUUGGCCUAGCUCAGGUCCACCGAGGUUUUGAGAUUGCCCUUUGCCCAAGGAGGAGUUGUGUCCUUGGCUCACCUGUCAUCUGCCUGUGACUGGACUUGAACCCUCGCACGUCUCAGCUGACAUCCUUGAUGCUGCUGGCUGCCUUCCUCGCCCUGUUUCCUCUCCAUGACUCCAGGGGUUUGAAGCACACAGGAGCUGGACAUGUCAAUUCUGUAGCUCUUCUCCCAAUACCACUGAAGGCCGUGAGCCUCUCUCCUGUUUCCAGCCUGCAGGUGCCCUGUUGCUGCUCUUCAUUCCAGCUUCUCCUCACUUUUCUCUCAGUCUCUUGAGCUUGGAAGCCUUAUUGUAGCUUGUGUCUCCUCCCUGGGCACUUGAGGUCAGGCUUUUGCCUUUUUGUCACAUUGAGCCACAUGCCUUUGAUACACAGUUGUAGCAAAGAAGGGAGGUGAUGAACUUGCUCACUUUCUUUUCUGAUUUCCCUCCCUACUCAUCCUGCACUCCCCACCGAAACCCAGAUAUCUUAUAGUCUAAGGCUUGUAGAGGAUUAAGGAAAGGAAUUGGAGAUGGGUUUUACUUAGUUCACAGAAAAGCUUUCUUUGGGAUUUUUCCUCCCCCUUAGGGCUUUUAAGUCUAGGUGAAGUGAAAGUUCACACAUGUGUUUGUUUGGUUGCUCUGUAAUUAGCUACUAGUUUUUAUCCCUAGACCUUCUCUGCUCCAGUGUCUUGUUCAUGUGUCCUGACCCCGUGUCCUUGAAUUCCCACUUUGCUUUGGGAUUUAAGUUAUUGUAUGUUGUCAACAAUAUUUAAAGAUGAAAAAGUCCUGAAGGAAACUUACCAGGUUCUUUCCUUUGGCUUUUUUUUUUUUUUCUUUCGAGGUACUGUAAAUUGUUAACUAGGGAUGCCAAGCAGGCUUGGUUCAAUGGCUAAACCUCUUAUUGUAUUACAGUGUAAUGCUGAUCUCAGCCUGGUCUCAAUGCCAGAGCACACAGAGACUUGAAUAAAACUGUUAUAACGAUUA